AAGCAGUAGCUACCCGCGGGAGCGGGGAGGGGUCCGGGUUCGAGCUUGUGUUCCCCCGGAAGGGUGAGUCUGGACGCGGGCGCGGAAGGAGCGCGGCCGGAGGUCCUCAGGAAGAAGCCGCGGGGACUGGCUGCGCUUGACAGGCUGCACUUGGAUGGGAGCACCUGGUGCCUCGGGACUGCUCCGAUGCCCGGGUCUGUGCUGAAUGUGUAAUAUGCGGAACUAUAUUGAAACAUUACAACCAUCUUUUGAUGGCAACACCCUGAGGACCUCCCUUUUCCAGAUGGGGAAACUGAGGCCCAGAAUUGCUAAGUGGCUUGCUUGAGUUGACACAGGGAGCUCCAGGACUCACCCUCAGCUGAGCCACCUGCCGGGAGCAUGCCUCUGCGCCACUGGGGGAUGGCCAGGGGCAGUAAGCCCGUUGGGGAUGGAGCCCAGCCCAUGGCUGCCAUGGGAGGCCUGAAGGUGCUUCUGCACUGGGCUGGUCCAGGCGGCGGGGAGCCCUGGGUCACUUUCAGUGAGUCAUCGCUGACAGCUGAGGAAGUCUGCAUCCACAUUGCACAUAAAGUUGGUAUCACUCCUCCUUGCUUCAAUCUCUUUGCCCUCUUCGAUGCUCAGGCCCAAGUCUGGUUGCCCCCAAACCACAUCCUAGAGAUCCCCAGAGAUGCAAGCCUGAUGCUAUAUUUCCGCAUAAGGUUUUAUUUCCGGAACUGGCAUGGCAUGAAUCCUCGGGAACCGGCUGUGUACCGUUGUGGGCCCCCAGGAACCGAGGCAUCCUCAGAUCAGACAGCACAGGGGAUGCAACUCCUGGACCCAGCCUCAUUUGAGUACCUCUUUGAGCAGGGCAAGCAUGAGUUUGUGAAUGACGUGGCAUCACUGUGGGAGCUGUCGACCGAGGAGGAGAUCCACCACUUUAAGAAUGAGAGCCUGGGCAUGGCCUUUCUGCACCUCUGUCACCUCGCUCUCCGCCAUGGCAUCCCCCUGGAGGAGGUGGCCAAGAAGACCAGCUUCAAGGACUGCAUCCCGCGCUCCUUCCGCCGGCAUAUCCGGCAGCACAGCGCCCUGACCCGGCUGCGCCUUCGGAACGUCUUCCGCAGGUUCCUGCGGGACUUCCAGCCGGGCCGACUCUCCCAGCAGAUGGUCAUGGUCAAAUACCUAGCCACACUCGAGCGGCUGGCACCCCGCUUCGGCACAGAGCGUGUGCCCGUGUGCCACCUGAGGCUGCUGGCCCAGGCCGAGGGGGAGCCCUGCUACAUCCGGGACAGUGGGGUGGCCCCUACAGACCCUGGCCCUGAGUCUGCUGCUGGGCCCCCAACCCACGAGGUGCUGGUGACAGGCACUGGUGGCAUCCAGUGGUGGCCAGUAGAGGAGGAGGUGAACAAGGAGGAGGGUUCUAGUGGCAGCAGUGGCAGGAACCCCCAAGCCAGCCUGUUUGGGAAGAAGGCCAAGGCUCACAAGGCAGUCGGCCAGCCGGCAGACAGGCCGCGGGAGCCACUGUGGGCCUACUUCUGUGACUUCCGGGACAUCACCCACGUGGUGCUGAAAGAGCACUGUGUCAGCAUCCACCGGCAGGACAACAAGUGCCUGGAGCUGAGCUUGCCUUCCCGGGCUGCGGCGCUGUCCUUCGUGUCGCUGGUGGACGGCUAUUUCCGCCUGACGGCCGACUCCAGCCACUACCUGUGCCACGAGGUGGCUCCCCCACGGCUGGUGAUGAGCAUCCGGGAUGGGAUCCACGGACCCCUGCUGGAGCCAUUUGUGCAGGCCAAGCUGCGGCCCGAGGACGGCCUGUACCUCAUUCACUGGAGCACCAGCCACCCCUACCGCCUGAUCCUCACAGUGGCCCAGCGUAGCCAGGCACCAGACGGCAUGCAGAGCUUGCGGCUCCGAAAGUUCCCCAUUGAGCAGCAGGACGGGGCCUUCGUGCUGGAGGGCUGGGGCCGGUCCUUCCCCAGCGUUCGGGAACUUGGGGCUGCCUUGCAGGGCUGCUUGCUGAGGGCCGGGGAUGACUGCUUCUCUCUGCGUCGCUGUUGCCUGCCCCAACCAGGAGAAACCUCCAAUCUCAUCAUCAUGCGGGGGGCUCGGGCCAGCCCCAGGACACUCAACCUCAGCCAGCUCAGCUUCCACCGGGUUGACCAGAAGGAGAUCACCCAGCUGUCCCACUUGGGCCAGGGCACAAGGACCAACGUGUAUGAGGGCCGCCUGCGAGUGGAGGGCAGCGGGGACCCUGAGGAGGGCAAGAUGGAUGACGAGGACCCCCUCGUGCCUGGCAGGGACCGUGGGCAGGAGCUACGAGUGGUGCUCAAAGUGCUGGACCCUAGUCACCAUGACAUCGCCCUGGCCUUCUACGAGACAGCCAGCCUCAUGAGCCAGGUCUCCCACACGCACCUGGCCUUCGUGCAUGGCGUCUGUGUGCGCGGCCCUGAAAAUAUCAUGGUGACAGAGUACGUGGAGCACGGACCCCUGGAUGUGUGGCUGCGGAGGGAGCGGGGCCAUGUGCCCAUGGCUUGGAAGAUGGUGGUGGCCCAGCAGCUGGCCAGCGCCCUCAGCUACCUGGAGAACAAGAACCUGGUUCAUGGUAAUGUGUGUGGCCGGAACAUCCUGCUGGCCCGGCUGGGGUUGGCAGAGGGCACCAGCCCCUUCAUCAAGCUGAGUGAUCCUGGCGUGGGCCUGGGCGCCCUCUCCAGGGAGGAGCGGGUGGAGAGGAUCCCCUGGCUGGCCCCCGAAUGCCUACCAGGUGGGGCCAACAGCCUAAGCACCGCCAUGGACAAGUGGGGGUUUGGCGCCACCCUCCUGGAGAUCUGCUUUGACGGAGAGGCCCCUCUGCAGAGCCGCAGUCCCUCCGAGGUAUGUCUAGGAGACCCUUGGGCCCUCCCCGCAGUGGGGGCCCCUCCAAGAAAUCCAGAGGACAGAAUCAGAGCUCAAAGCUGCAUCCCUUCUGGCCUCGUGACUUCAAGUCUCUCUGGGCUACCAGCAGGUGGGCCACUCGCUGGGGCUCAAUGUAGUCCCAGCCUUUUUAGGUCCUUGUGGAAGUCACUUGUGCCUGGCACACAGAAGAAGGAGCAUUUCUACCAGAGGCAGCACCGGCUGCCCGAGCCCUCCUGCCCACAGCUGGCCACACUCACCAGCCAGUGUCUGACCUAUGAGCCAACCCAGAGGCCAUCAUUCCGCACCAUCCUGCGUGACCUCACCCGGCUGCAGCCCCACAAUCUUGCUGACGUCUUGACUGUGAACCCGGACUCACCGGCGUCGGACCCUACGGUUUUCCACAAGCGCUAUUUGAAAAAGAUCCGAGAUCUGGGCGAGGGUCACUUCGGCAAGGUCAGCUUGUACUGCUACGAUCCGACCAACGACGGCACUGGCGAGAUGGUGGCGGUGAAAGCCCUCAAGGCAGACUGCGGCCCCCAGCACCGCUCGGGCUGGAAGCAGGAGAUUGACAUUCUGCGCACGCUCUACCACGAGCACAUCAUCAAGUACAAGGGCUGCUGCGAGGACCAAGGCGAGAAGUCGCUGCAGCUGGUCAUGGAGUACGUGCCCCUGGGCAGCCUCCGAGACUACCUGCCCCGGCACAGCAUCGGGCUGGCCCAGCUGCUGCUCUUCGCCCAGCAGAUCUGCGAGGGCAUGGCCUAUCUGCACGCGCAGCACUACAUCCACCGAGACCUAGCCGCGCGCAACGUGCUGCUGGACAACGACAGGCUGGUCAAGAUCGGGGACUUUGGCCUAGCCAAGGCCGUGCCCGAAGGCCACGAGUACUACCGCGUGCGCGAGGAUGGGGACAGCCCCGUGUUCUGGUAUGCCCCAGAGUGCCUGAAGGAGUAUAAGUUCUACUAUGCGUCAGAUGUCUGGUCCUUCGGGGUGACCCUGUAUGAGCUGCUGACGCACUGUGACUCCAGCCAGAGCCCCCCCACGAAAUUCCUUGAGCUCAUAGGCAUUGCUCAGGGUCAGAUGACAGUUCUGAGACUCACUGAGUUGCUGGAACGAGGGGAGAGGCUGCCACGGCCCGACAAAUGUCCCUGUGAGGUCUAUCAUCUCAUGAAGAACUGCUGGGAGACAGAGGCGUCCUUUCGCCCAACCUUCGAGAACCUCAUACCCAUUCUGAAGACAGUCCAUGAGAAGUACCAAGGCCAGGCCCCUUCAGUGUUCAGCGUGUGCUGAGGCACAAUGGCAGCCCUGCCUGGGAGGACUGGACCAGGCAGUGGCUGCAGAGGGAGCCUCCUGCUCCCUGCUCCAGGAUGAAACCAAGAGGGGGAUGUCAGCCUCACCCACACCGUGUGCCUUACUCCUGUCUAGAGACCCCACCUCUGUGAACUUAUUUUUCUUUCUUGGCCGUGAGCCUAACCAUGAUCUUGAGGGACCCAACAUUUGUAGGGGCACUAAUCCAGCCCUUAAAUCCCCCAGCUUCCAAACUUGAGGCCCACCAUCUCCACCAUCUGGUAAUAAACUCAUGUUUUCUCUG